AUGGCUCUCCACUUGUCCCGAGUGUCACGACGACGAGGAUGGGGACCAUAUCUUCGGAGCCUGAGGAUCCAACACAGGUCCAGCCCUGUGCAGCCGCCCGCCAAGCCGCCAGAGGACGAGCCGGACGCCGAAGGCUACGAGUGGACGAUUGCAGUUAGUUUCCAACUCGCCGACUUCGCGCCCCUCCACUGGCUCCGGCUUGAUGGUCCCGGCUUCGGGGUGCUCUCGACCGGACCAGAGAGGUGGGAAGUUUGGGGGCACCCGCUGUGGGUGUCCCGUUUCCGGGGCUGGGCUCCGGGGAGCCGGCGCGGCGCCCGCUCCCUGCCCGCCAGCCCUUUGGGAGCUCAGGCGCGGGCAGCCGCUUGUGUUCCUGGGAAGGGCGGAGCUGCGUCCCGGGGAGACACGCCUUGCAGCCGGCAGCCUAGUCGCUCCCCGCUGGCCGGCCGCUCCGUGAGGGCCCCGCAGCGGAGGGUCGGGGCUGGGGCGGGCUGGAGAGGGGGCCCCGGGCUGGGGCCGGUUCGGCCUCCCGGGUGGCGCGCGGGCCGAAGAACUAGGAGGACCGCCGGGCCGGGCCGCUUGUCCUUUGGAAAAACCUUGGCGGUUCCUCCUCUGGUGUCCGUGGACCCCGCCGUGGCGUUCUCCAGGGCCGCGGACCUUUGCCCACCGGUCGCGCCAGCUGUCCUGGAGCAGAAAGGACCCCCCUCCUCCCGGACCGAGCCCCGAGCCCCGAGCCCCAUGGAGCAGGCAAGCGCCGGAGUCCCGAGGCUAAGGCCCGGCCGGCGGGCGCUCUGGCACCUUUUCCCGCCCCCGAGGGUGCCUGUCCGGCCCGGCCGGGACUGGCUGGGAAACCGAGGCCGGAAGAGGUCGCAGUCCAGCAAGGAAUCGGGGCAGCUCUUCCGUGGUUCCUUGCAGACCCCAGGUCAGGCCAGAAAACACCUCUAUGGCCCUUCCCUGUGUCCCACCACCAGAUAGGACCUCAAAGGCCUGGGGUCCCCAGGAUGGCCCUCAAACCGACUGGUGCCCUUGCAGGCUGCCACCCUCCAAGUCCUGCUUCUCUCUAGAGAUGGGCAGGAGCACCAGCCCUCACCUGGCACCAGCACUUUACUGGUGGAACAUAAUAUGGUCUAAGAAGAGAUUUUUCCAGCAAGAGGCCAUCUCUGCAAAUCACCUGUGAGGCAGACCUGUGGCAAUUUUAUGACUCAGCUGGCCACCGGGAUUGUAGCUGGGUUCUGCCGCUUGUUGAAACCUACUCAGUGUUCUCCUUCCCUAAGUAGGACAAGACCGUAUCCUGCCUUUAAGAUUUAUAGAAUAAAAACUGAAAACUCUUUGGGGAAGAAAAUCUUCCCGAACAGAUAGCCCAGGGCAUUUUGAAAAUCCCUUAGGAAGUUCUCUGUUUCACUUGGGUACCUUUGUCCUUGGACUUUGGUGAUGUGGUUUGACCCCAGCCAGAGAGUGCAGGGAACAACAGCAAAAGGCAGGACAAAGACUGACUCGUGAGAGGAGGCCCAGGAACAGGGGGGCAUCGUGAAUGAGGAGGACGUGGGGGCCCAAGAAAGUGAGCUCUUGCGCACUCAGUCACCAGCCCCCUUCUGGGGUCCAAGCUGUGUCCCCUUCUCUAAAGAGGUAAGCCCUGAGUCAUGGGAAGAUGGAAACCGGGGCUGAUGAGACAGGAUGUUUUUUAAGCACCGUGGUAUCUUGUUGACUUGCACAUGCACGGGGGUCUUGGGUAACCACAGGGCUCAGGGUAUUUGCAGGAACAGUUCAAGUGCUCACUUGUCUUGGGGCUGUUUAUGGGGAAGUGGUUUCCACAGUGAGAGGACGUGAGAUAUUGUUGUCACCCCGGACCACACUUAGCUAGUUCCUUCUCACUAAAGCUCUGUAGUCAUAUUUUCCCUGGCAGAGCAGAAACUUCUAUGUUAUCCCACAGCUGUUCUAACGGCGUAGACUUGACUUAUGCAAUGAUGCCAGGAGUCCUGAGCAGCACAGCCCAACUUCAAUCACACACAGAUGGACAGAGCUGUAUUAGCAAAGCCUGAGCUACUGAGCGAUGAGAGUACAGCCAGGCUUUCAGACAUCUGUUCAUUCAAGAGAGAUAUGCGCUAAGCCAAGGACCUAAAGAUGUGUUUAAUGUGGGUGCUAAUAUGCAUAAGGAACCUUGAAAUAAAUGUUCUUAGCCUUUGGCCAA